ACCACUGUGGGCAGCCUCACUUGGCUGCCGCCCCGAGACCCCAGCCCGUACCUGGGCUUCGCGCCCGCCAAGUGGGCCCAGCCCUGGCUCCUGCGCCCUGUGGCGGCCACCUCCAUCGCCUUGCUUUCCCUUCGGGCACUGGGGGUCGCUCAGGGCGGGACAUGGGUGAACGGAAGUGGAAGCUGUGAGCGUCGCAGCCCGAGGCGCCGAGGCCUGAGGCGCCGUCGGGGCCACAGCGACGCUCGCAUGGAGAGCGCUGGGCGCUGGGCUGUGCACCGACGGCUAACCUGGACCCACGGUCUCUGCGGGGCGGGAGCUUUGCAGAACCGACUGGCCGACUGGGGCGCGGGAACAUGAGGCUUGGCUAGGAGCCCGCUGCGGGCCAGGCGCGCGGUGCGCAGGCAUACCCGGGUCGCGGGUGAACACCGCGGAGCCCCGGGACUUGGUAAUUGGCGCGAGCGGGUGCGCGCAUGCGCGGGACGGCGGCGGGCACGUGGCGAGGCGCAGGGCGGCGCCGCGCGGGAAGCUCCCCAGUGCCCUGGAGGCCUGCUGGCUGGACGACCCCCUGCCUCUGGUACCAAGUGUGACCAAGGCUGGCGCCACCAUGGCUCUGCUGCCGUCACCUCCUCCCUUUAGCAUUGAGCAGCCCCGGAGGGGCUAGCCCUGAGGCUGACCUGCCCAGAGUCCCCACCAUCGCGCUGCUUAGUGGCCUCUCCCUGCAGCCUGUCGUUGCUGGUGGCGGCAUGGUCUUCUGUCUGUCGAGCGAGGAGCCGCGCCGCCCGCUGCGAAGCGACAUGGUCCACUUCCAGGCCUCGGAAGUCCAGCAGCUGCUACACAACAAGUUCGUGGUCAUCUUGGGGGACUCCAUUCAGAGGGCUGUGUACAAGGACCUGGUGCUCUUGCUCCAGAAAGACUCACUGCUCACAGCUGCCCAGCUGAAAGCCAAGGGGGAGCUGAGCUUUGAACAGGACCAGCUGGUGGCUGGGGGCCAGCUGGGCGAGCUGCACAACGGGACACAGUAUCGUGAGGUCCGCCAGUUCUGCUCGGGCUCUGGCCACCACCUUGUGCGCUUCUACUUCCUCACUCGUGUUUACUCCGAGUACCUUGAGGAUGUUCUGGAAGAGCUGACAUAUGGACCUGCCCCGGACCUGGUGAUCAUCAACUCCUGCCUCUGGGAUCUCUCCAGAUAUGGUCGCUGCUCAAUGGAGAGCUACCGGGAGAACCUGGAGCGGGUGUUUGUGCGCAUGGACCAAGUAUUGCCAGACUCCUGCCUGCUGGUGUGGAACAUGGCGAUGCCCCUCGGGGAACGUAUCACUGGGGGUUUCCUCCUGCCAGAGCUCCAGCCCCUGGCAGGCUCCCUGCGGCGGGAUGUGGUUGAAGGGAACUUCUACAGUGCUACGCUGGCCGGGGACCACUGCUUUGAUGUCCUAGACCUCCACUUUCACUUCCGGCAUGCAGUACAGCACCGUCAUCGGGAUGGUGUCCACUGGGACCAGCAUGCACACCGCCACCUCUCACACCUGCUUCUGACCCAUGUGGCUGACGCCUGGGGCGUGGAGCUGCCCAAGCGUGGCUAUCCCCCUGACCCGUGGAUUGAGGACUGGGCAGAGAUGAAUCAUCCAUUCCAGGGAAGCCAUAGGCAGACCCCAGACUUCGGGGAGCACCUGGCCUUGCUCCCACCCCCACCUUCUUCUUUGCCUCCUCCCAUGCCUUUUCCCUACCCGCUUCCUCAGCCCUCGCCACCUCCCCUCUUCCCACCCCUGCCCCAGGAUACCCCUUUUUUCCCAGGCCAGCCCUUCCCACCCCAUGAAUUCUUCAACUAUAAUCCAGUGGAGGACUUCUCGAUGCCACCCCACUUAGGAUGUGGCCCUGGAGUGAACUUUGUGCCUGGCCCUCUGCCACCUCCAAUCCCUGGCCCUAAUCCCCAUGGUCAGCACUGGGGCCCAGUGGUCCACCGGGGGAUGCCACGCUAUGUUCCUAACAGCCCCUACCAUGUGCGGAGAAUGGGGGGGCCCUGCAGGCAGCGGCUCAGACACUCAGAGAGACUGAUCCACACAUACAAACUGGACAGACGGCCUCCUGCCCAUUCGGGGACAUGGCCUGGGUAGACUGGAUCUUGGGCUGGGACUGGAUGUGCCAAUGGCCCUUCAGGGCCUGCCUGGCACCUCAGGUACUGGGCUAGGGUGUCUGCUAUGCCUGGUAUUGUUCUUGUCCAUUGCUGUCACCAAUAAAGGCAUGGAAGAACAGAGUGACAAA